ACAAGCAAGGGUGUGCGGCUCUGAGACGUGCGUUGCUGCUUGUGGGUGUGAGACAUCCUAGCUCCUCUUCCCCUUCCGUGAGUCCCUCCUUUCCUCGCAGACCCCACUUGUCGUGGCUGGCUGCCGCCGCAGCUCUUGUGCGAAGCCAGCAGUGCGCGUGCGCGCGGGCACGGGCGCGCGACCGUCGGGUCCCCGCGCUCCCUCCCCCUCCCGCUCCUCUAUAACUUGGCUGGCGUGGAGGAGGCGCCGCCGGAGUCGGAGGGCGGGGAGCUAGGAGGAGGGAGCUCGAGAGUUGUGGAGACUAGUGACUGGGAGAAGUCGCAGCCCGCUCAGGCCCGCGCCUUCCCGCUCCCCGUCUUCCUCUCUCACACACCUACUCCGCCCUCCGCCCCAGCCCGCGCGCUAGCUCCUUCUCUCGCCCGGGGUUCCUGCCGGUAGCUCUCCGGGUCUUGGCGCGGCGGGGGCGCCCCGGGGGUGCCCUCGCCCUCCCGUUGCGGGCGGGCGGGCGGUAUGUGGCGCCUGGUGCCCCCGAAGCUGGGCCGCCUGUCCCGCUCGCUGAAGCUGGCGGCGCUGGGCAGCCUGUUGGUGCUGAUGGUGCUGCACUCGCCGUCGCUGCUCGCCUCUUGGCAGCGCAACGAACUGACCGACCGGCGCUUCCUGCAGCUCAAUAAGUGCCCGGCGUGCUUCGGCACGAGCUGGUGCCGCCGCUUCCUCAACGGGCAGGUGGUAUUCGAGGCGUGGGGCCGCUUGCGCCUGCUGGACUUCCUCAACGUGAAGAACGUGUACUUCGCGCAGUACGGCGAGCCCCGCGAGGGCGGCCGCCGCCGAGUGGUGCUCAAGCGCCUCGGCUCGCAGCGCGAGCUGGCGCAGCUCGACCAGAGCAUCUGCAAGCGGGCCACCGGCCGGCCCCGCUGCGACCUGCUGCAGGCCAUGCCCCGGACCGAGUUCGCGCGCCUCAACGGCGACGUGCGUCUGCUCACGCCCGAGGCGGUGGAGGGCUGGUCGGACCUGGUGCACUGCCCCUCGCAGCGCCUUCUCGACCGCCUGGUGCGCCGCUACGCGGAGACCAAGGACUCGGGCAGCUUCCUGCUUCGCAACCUCAAGGACUCGGAGCGCAUGCAGCUGCUGCUGACCCUGGCCUUCAACCCCGAGCCGCUGGUGCUACAGAGUUUUCCGUCUGAUGAAGGUUGGCCAUUUGCAAAGUAUCUUGGAGCUUGUGGAAGAAUGGUGGCUGUAAAUUAUGUUGGAGAAGAACUGUGGAGUUACUUUAAUGCGCCAUGGGAAAAACGAGUUGACCUCGCUUGGCAAUUAAUGGAAAUAGCAGAACAGCUUACAAACAAUGACUUUGAAUUUGCACUCUACCUCCUGGACGUCAGCUUUGACAAUUUUGCAGUUGGUCCUAGAGAUGGGAAGGUAAUCAUUGUGGAUGCUGAAAAUGUUUUGGUUGCUGACAAAAGAUUAAUUAGACAAAAUAAACCUGAAAAUUGGGAUGUAUGGUAUGAAAGCAAGUUUGAUGACUGUGAUAAGGAGGCUUGCUUAUCAUUUUCAAAAGAAAUUCUUUGUGCUCGUGCCACUGUGGACCACAAUUACUAUGCUGUUUGUCAGAACCUCUUAUCCAGACAUGCCACCUGGCGUGGCACUUCUGGAGGACUCCUUCAUGAUCCACCAAGUGAAAUUGCCAAAGAUGGCCGGCUCGAGGCCUUGCUGGAUGAGUGUGCCAACCCAAAGAAGCGCUAUGGCAGAUUCCAGGCUGCAAAAGAACUGCGUGAAUACCUAGCACAAUUAAGUAACAACGUGAGGUAGUCUAUGGUGAACUUUUCUUUUUUUCUCCAUUUAAACAGCACUGGCUAAAACUAAACCACCAAAAAACGAUCUGAAAAAAUGAAAUUUGGAAGUGUUACAUUCAGAGGAUGAUAAACUUGCACUGAUAGAUCUUAAUGUUAACAUCCAUCAAAAUAAGACAUUACUUCAAAAAUCACAUGAUGCUUCUGCAAAUAAGUAUGUUCUUAUACUUUGGAGGCUUGAGCUGUCAUCAGCUGCUCCCCACUACCCCGGAAUGCUUGAGUGGAUUAAUGAAUAUUGUUAAGCUAUUGGAAAUGAGUCUGAUAGUACAUUGGCUUGUGUAUCAAAGGGUACUUGGUACUUAGUUUGCAUUUACUAUCAUGAUUUUGUGAAUCUCUUGCAUUUACUUUGAAUGUCAAGUCAGAUUGGUCUGUUUUAUAGGCCGCUUUUUCCUUCUGAUGUGUAGGGUUUUUUCCCCCUUUUUUUUUUUAAUUAAAUUUUGAAAAUUCAGGUUACUGUAGGUGUUCAUUUAAAUUUUUAAUAGUUGUCAUUCAGUGCUAUUUGGUACAUAUUUACUGUUAGGGCAGGAUUCCCAGGUUUACUGUGUUUUUUUUUUUUUUUUUUAAAGAAAGCUAAAUAUUACAUUAUGUAAAUACUUCUUUUCACCAACUUCUGUAGUUUCACCAUUGCAUGGUGUCAUUUCAGGUUAUUUAACAGUUAUAUCCCUCUAUGCCAAUAAUUAGAAGUGUACACUAAACAUGAAGUUUGGCAUAUGUUGCAAAAUGUCAUUUUAUCUUUUCUAAAGGCUUUAAGAAGAAUAUACUAGAAUCUAUAUAUUGAUGUUAAUUUUGAUUCAGAAAAAAAAUACAACCCAGUAUCUAAAAAGUGUUAACUAGUCCAAGAUAGUAAUGCAUAUGCCAAAGAAAUAUUACACCUAAUCUCAUGUUUAGAAUUUAAAAUAGAAUUGGUCAGCUACUUAUUCUUACCACCCUACUUCCAGUAUUUUAGCUCUGUCAUUAUUAAAUUCAGAUCUUCCUGAUUAUUUUUUCUGUUGAAAGUUAAACUACUGCUUUCAAGUAAUUUAAAGUUAUCCUACCUUUUAUUCAUGGGUAGUUUUGCAAAAUUAACAUGGUAGCCAUUGUUUGAAUUUAAUCGGGCAUCAUAACUUUUCAUUUAUUGAGGAACUAAUCAUUAUUACUAUAAAGCAUACAAAUUAGCCAGUCAGCACACUUUGGUCUUCUUUACCUAAGGGUUAAACAUCAGAACAUCAAAUUUAAUUAUUUGCAUAGAAAUGUGUGGGCUCUUUAUAUAAGUUGACUAUCACUAACAGGUAAUAUUUUUCUGUUUGAAGUUGUUACUUUUGUUUACAGCAAAGUUUGAUGUAGUGUGCAGUAGUGAGCUCUAGACUGAUCUUUUUCUAAAUCAGAAAGUGAUUAAAGUAUGCACAACCAAAGGCAGGUUUUUCUUUUUCAUUUAUUCAGCAACUAUUUAUUAAGCAUCAACUCUGUGCCAGGCACGUUACUAGCUGCUACAUACUGUCUGAACAUGACAUACGGUUAAGUAACUUUACAAUUAUUAUCAAAUACUUCAAUGUAGAUAUUUCUUAAGUUGAAAUAGCAUUAACUAGGAUAAUGCUUUCAUGUUAUUUUAUUGUCUUGUGAUAGAAAUUCAACUUGUACCAUCUAAAACUAGGUUGCUAUAAAAAUAGGAGGAUGAAGUCAAUAAAGUUUAUGCCAGUUUAAAAACUGGAAGGAAAAGGUAAGAGCUCUCCAUUAUAAAAUAGUUGCAUUCGGUUAAUUUUUACACAUUAGUGCAUUGCGUAUAUCAACUGGCCCUCAAUGAAGCAUUUAAGUGCUUGGAAUUUUACUAAACUGACUUUUUUGCAACUUUGGGAGAUUUUUGAGGGGAGUGUUGAAAAUUGCCAAACACUCACCUCUUACUCAAAACUUCAAAUAAAAUACACAUUUUCAAGAGGGAGCACCUUUUAUAUUUGAUAAGUUUUCAUUAUAAACCUUAUAAUACCAGUCACAAAGAGGUUGUCUGUCUAUGGUUUAGCAAACAUUUGCUUUUCUUUUUGGAAGUGUGAUUGCAAUUGCAGAACAGAAAGUGAGAAAACACUGCCAGCGGUGAUUGCUACUUGAGGUAGUUUUUUACAACUACCAUUUCCCCUCCAUGAAAUUAUGUGAAAUUUAUUUUAUCUUUGGGAAAAGUUGAGAAGAUAGUAAAAGAAUUAGGAAUUUAAAAUUACAGGGAAAAAUAUGUAAGUGAAAAGCAAUAAAUAUUUUGUUCACUUUGCUAUCAAGAUGUUCACUAUCAGAUAUUUAUUAUAUGGCAGCAAUUUAUAUUUUUAAUCAUUGCCCAUUAAUAGACGCAGUAAAAUAUUUUUGAAUCAGACAUUUGGGGUUUGUAUGUGCAUUAAAAUUGUCUUUUGUACUGUAAGUUACUGUUAAUUUGAAUAUUUUAUUGAACUGUCUCCCUGUGCCUUUAUAAUAUAAAGUUGUUUCUACAACUUUUAAUGAUCUUAAUAAAGAAUACUUUAAGAAUCACA